GGUCCGGGCGGGUCAGGCCUCUGAGGGGAUGGCAUGGGCGGAGACUGCAGGCUUCUGGGCCUGAGAGGGCUGGAGCUGGCUUUCCGGAGCCGGGGGCGGGGCGCGGGCGGGCCUCAGCUGUGGUUACUGGUGACAGGUCGCCUGACUGGGCUCCUCCCCGGGCCCGCCCCGACAGGUUUGUCUUGUGACCGCGGGCGGCCGCUGCUUCUUUCCCGAGCUUGGAACUUCGUUAUCCGCGAUGCGUUUCCUGGCAGCUACAUUCCUGCUCCUGGCGCUCAGCACCGCUGCCCAGGCCGAACCGGUGCAGUUCAAGGACUGCGGUUCUGUGGAUGGAGUUAUAAAGGAAGUGAAUGUGAGCCCAUGCCCCACCCAACCCUGCCAGCUGAGCAAAGGACAGUCUUACAGCGUCAAUGUCACCUUCACCAGCAAUAUUCAGUCUAAAAGCAGCAAGGCCGUGGUGCAUGGCAUCCUGAUGGGCGUCCCAGUUCCCUUUCCCAUUCCUGAGCCUGAUGGUUGUAAGAGUGGAAUUAACUGCCCUAUCCAAAAAGACAAGACCUAUAGCUACCUGAAUAAACUACCAGUGAAAAGCGAAUAUCCCUCUAUAAAACUGGUGGUGGAGUGGCAACUUCAGGAUGACAAAAACCAAAGUCUCUUCUGCUGGGAAAUCCCAGUACAGAUCGUAAGUCUAUCUGGGGGUGAGAGGGCAUGGGUGGAGGGAAGAAAGUGGAGGAGAAAUCAGACUGAAACUAAAUCAGUGCCAUAAGAUAAAAGGAAUUUCAAGACUGCUGUUUUAUGCCUCUCAACCUCUAAAAGCAUCUGAGACCCUAUUUCCUGAGAGCUCAGAACUGUUGCCUUUGUAAUAUCCUUUGUUAAAAAAAAAAAAGGUUGAAGGAAAGAAGAGAGAGUGAGACUGUAGAGAUUGAUUUAACUGUCUUCAUUGGUUUUUUUCUGUCGGAGUAAGGAAGGUCCAGCCAGACAGGACCUGAAGGAGGUUGCUUAGGAAUGUCUGAUAACUUGCCCUAGGGUUAUUGCCCUGACAGUGGAGGAAAGGUUCCAAACCACUUCCACUGAGCUGGGACAUUACAUCCACAGGUUUCUCAUCUCUAAGUGCCUCAUUGAGUUCGGUGCAUCUGGCCAAUGAGUCUGCUGAGACUCUUGACAGCACCUCCAGCUCUGCUGCUUCAACAACAGUGACUUGCUCUCCAAUGGUAUCCAGUGAUUCGUUGAAGAGGAGGUGCUCUGUAGCAGAAACUGAGCUCCGGGUGGCUGGUUCUCAGUGGUUGUCUCAUGUCUCUUUUUCUGUCUUAGGUGGUUUCAUUAAAUGCAGCACUUGGUUAGCAGAUGUUUAAUUUUUUUUUUAACAACAUUAACUUGUGGCCUCUUUCUACACCUGGAAAUUUACUCUUGAAUAAAUAAAAACUCGUUUGUCUUGUCUUCUGCAUGUGG